UUUCCUCCGGCGGCGCCGGCGGCCGCAGAACUUCCGGGUCGGCGCGGAGGCGGGGCGGAGGCGCCGCGGCGGCUGUUAUUGUUCGGCUGGGCUCGGUCGGGCGCUGUCUCCCUCGGCUCUGCGGGUGUCAGUUCGUCCGGCUUCCUCACAGCCCCUCACUCCCGGCGGCUGACAGCAGCAGCGGCGGCGGCGGGCGGCGCCUGGCGUUUCGAGGCUGAGCGGCACCGGGGUUGGGGCGCGGAGGAGGAGCAGCAGCGGGAGGAGGAGCCGUGUGCCCUGGCACUGAGCGGCCGCGGCCAUGGCGUACGCCUAUCUCUUCAAGUACAUCAUAAUCGGCGACACAGGUGUAGAGUUCGGUGCUCGAAUGAUAACUAUUGAUGGGAAACAGAUAAAACUUCAGAUAUGGGAUACGGCAGGGCAAGAAUCCUUUCGUUCCAUCACAAGGUCGUAUUACAGAGGUGCAGCAGGAGCUUUACUAGUUUACGAUAUUACACGGAGAGAUACAUUCAACCACUUGACAACCUGGUUAGAAGAUGCCCGCCAGCAUUCCAAUUCCAACAUGGUCAUUAUGCUUAUUGGAAAUAAAAGUGAUUUAGAAUCUAGAAGAGAAGUAAAAAAAGAAGAAGGUGAAGCUUUUGCACGAGAACAUGGACUCAUCUUCAUGGAAACGUCUGCUAAGACUGCUUCCAAUGUAGAAGAGGCAUUUAUUAAUACAGCAAAAGAAAUUUAUGAAAAAAUUCAAGAAGGAGUCUUUGACAUUAAUAAUGAGGCAAAUGGCAUUAAAAUUGGCCCUCAGCAUGCUGCUACCAAUGCAACACAUGCAGGCAAUCAGGGAGGACAGCAGGCUGGGGGCGGCUGCUGUUGAGUCUGUUUUUACUGUCUAGCUGCCCAACGGGGCCUACUCACUUAUUCUUUCACCCCCUCUCCUCCUGCUCAGCUGAGACAUGAAACUAUUUGAAAUGGCUUUAUGUCACAGAAGACUUUAAUCCGUCAAAUUCUUGUAUAACUUUGAAUAAAUGGUUAAUGUUCACUUAAAAGACAGAUUUUGGAGAUUGUAUUCAUAUCUAUUUGCAUUUGAUUUCUAGGUCAAUUGAUGUGAUUAUUUUUGUUAAAUGUUGUCUUGUGCCCUUAACUACGAACUGAAUUGUAUUAAACACUACAAAGUCAUCUUGAGUAUUUUAAAUCGGUUUGUGUAGUUAGGUUUCCCAACAUCUGUGGUUACCUAAUGUUUAAUAUUAUAGAACUGUCCUCAGAAACUUUGUCAAUUUUCACGGCUAUAAGGAAACAGAAGGACUCUUUUAAUUCUGUAUUUAUCAUUUACUUUCUGUAUAUAUAGUUUAAUAACCUGCUUGGGUGUAAUUUGCCAAGCUUGAAUUCUUUAAUGCAUUUGCAUAAAUUCUAUACUGUUUAGAGCUUAAAGCUACAGAAGCAUUGUUAGGAAUUGCUUGGACACUGAAUUUUAAACUUUUUGACAUUGUUAACAAGCAUGUUCAUCUUUUCUUGUCACUAGUCCAAGAAAAAUAUGCUUAAUGUAUAUUACAAAGGCUUUGUAUAUGUUAACCUGUUUUAAUGCCAAAAGUUUGCUUUGUCCACAAUUUCCUUAAGACCUCUUCAGAAAGGGAUUUGUUUGCCUUAAUGAAUACUGUUGGGAAAAAACACAGUAUAAUGAGUGAAAAGGGCAGAAGCAAGAAAUUUCUACAUCUUAGCGACUCCAAGAAGAAUGAGUAUCCACAUUUAGAUGGCACAUUAUGAGGACUUUAAUCUUUCCUUAAACACAAUAAUGUUUUCUUUUUUCUUUUAUUCACAUGAUUUCUAAGUAUAUUUUUCAUGCAGGACAGUUUUUCAACCUUGAUGUACAGUGACUGUGUAAAAUUUUUCUUUCAGUGGCAACCUCUAUAAUCUUUAAAAUAUGGUGAGCAUCUUGUCUGUUUUGAAGGGGAUAUGACAAUAAAUCUAUCAGAUGGAAAAUCCUGUUACAAAGUAGAAAAGCUUUAGUAAUUUACUCAGUGUGGUGGUUUUAUCCUUUUUUUCUUUUUCUCCCUUGGUCUAUAAUGAAAUUGUUACAGCAGUGCAAAAUAAAAUCCUAUGUAUAAAAGUGUUCUUUUUUUUUAUUAUGACCACCUCUUUUUUAAUGUAUUUUUAGUCCACUUACAGCUUUUACAUGGGUUUAAGCAUGUUUUUUAAAAGGGUCAGAAUGGUUAACACUCAACCCUUUUUAAAAAUUUUGCUAAAAUGCGACAAAUCUCACCAUACUGAAAUUAUUUUUGUUGAUGGUGUAAGCAGUGUAAGCAAGUGUUUUCUCCUGAACUAGCACAAAAGCACUUAUGCCUGAAAGAAAGCAUAAAGAAGUUCUAACUCUGAAACUAACUACUUUCAUUUCGCUCAUGGCCUUCAACUUUCUACAGGUCUUCCCUGAAGAUUCAGCAGUACUCUCUCAAAGGUUUGACAGUACUCUUGUGGGAAAUCACCAAAUGCUGUCAUAGUUUUGUUUUAACUGUCUCCUUGAGGGCAGAGGGAAGGGUGAGAGAAAAUCUGUUUUCAUGGGUAUUUGUAGUACAGCCUUUUUUUCUUUCAAGUGGCUGUAUCAAAUUCACUGGUCUUACUAAUCACUGUCUUUACCAGUGAGUACAAAAAGUUAAGGCAACUAGGACAGGUACUGCUCUAUACCAAGAAGAGAAUGAUUCUUUGGAAAUUGUUAUUUUUAAGCUUCUGUUAAUUUUUCCAGAAGUUUAGUGCGUUUCUUUUCCAUACUUUCUCCCCUAAUUCUUUUAUUUGAAGAAGAGAACUUAAUGGCAAAUAAACAACAAACCAGGACAUGCAUUUUAAUACCCUAAGGAAAAAUGGAACCCUCAAAUAUAACUCCUCCCACAACCACCCUAAUGUGCCUCAGUCUGGGGCAGCAGGUGGACUUCUCAAUAGUUCUUUUCCACAUUCUCUACAAAUCACAUCUACCGUUAAGGAAUAUGUUAUGAAUCCUUUCUGUUAAUUGAGAAAGCAAUGUUAUUGUCUGUGAUUUCCAGUCUUUGCUCAUUUUAUUAUCCCUGUCAAAUAAUGUAAUAUUGGUACCUGCAGUUGAAUUUGUAAUAUUGUAAUUGAAUUUUUAGUUGAUCUUCGAUCAGUUUUUAUAGCAUCUAUGGACAUAGAAAAUCAGUCACUGAAAAAAAUAAACACAGCUUUCAAUGUCUCACUCAACAUGUAACAUUCAAAAUUGUGAUCUUCAUAAAGACAUUGUUACCAUUCGUCUUGCAAAUUUAAGACAACUGAAUGAAAAGCCAAUUUUUUGAAAGAAUGUGGCAUAUAAUUAGAUAUACAACUGAAACAGGAUAUACAACUGCAUACAAUUUGUUUUUAAUGAUAUUUUAAAAUAGCCUGUUAGCAGGAAAAUAGUCCCUAUUUAUCUGCUAAUGGUCAAAAAGAGUUAGGAUAUAAAUCGUACCAAAAUGUUUCCAAUCACUCAGAAAAACUGAUUCAUGUCUGGCUUUGCAACACCUUAAACAUUUAUUCUGUCAUAGAUAGUAAAGCCCCAUCUCAGUUUAUUUAGUCCUGAGGUUGGCAGCAUGGGGUUUGACUAUAUGAGCUAAAAGAUACACAAAGAGAUAACGCUGUUUCAUAAUAAACAGGAAUUGACUAUACAAAUAGGUAAACCAGCAUAUCUACCUGUAUUUCUCAGAGUUUAGAUGUGUGCUUUAUGUUUACAUUAAAAUAAAGCCUAACGCCACAGUAGAUCAUCUCAUACUGCA